CCCUUGGUCCCUGUGGGGUCCCCUCCCCUCCGCUGGCCACCAUUUACCUCGCCUGACGAUGUCACCCACCCUUUUGCUGUCCCUGCUCACGGCACUCGCUUUAGGGUUUCCACUACCCCCACCCGUCUCUCCUCCAGUCUACACUUGUGUGAGGUGUUGGGGGACAGCCAGUCUUCCGGACUCUUCUCCCACCCUCUGGUGGGGUCGCUGUCCUGGAGUUGGGCUCGAGAGUGCUUUCAGGGCGGCGUGGUGAGCAGGACCUAGGGUGCUGCGGGCACCCUCCCCCUCGGACCGCGCUCAGGUCGGGGAAACAUCCCCUGUGCCCUCUCCCCUACAUUUCUCCUCUGGCAGGCCCUGCAUAUGGUGCCCCGUGGGUGCUGUUGACCAGGGGCCCUCCCAGCACACCUGCAAUGGCUGGACCUUAGCUGCCGCCUCUGUAAGACAACUGACAUCACACCUGGUAUCAAAGUUUAGACUGUUCAGGAUGUAGGUGCAAAAGUACACAGGAUGUGGACGAUUGCUGCGGUUUGUCCAGCAUUUUAUGGCUGAUAGAGUAUCUCUCCACUGUGUGAGCCUCUCAGCAGCGCAUGGGGUGGCGAGGACAGGUGUGGUUUUGUCCCUGUGGAACAGAUGGGGAAACUGAAGCUCCAGAGCAUCCGCAGUGUCAUGCAGAAGUACCUGGAGGACCGGGGCGAGGUGACCUUUGAGAAGAUCUUUUCCCAGAAGCUGGGGUACCUGCUCUUCCGAGACUUCUGCCUGAACCACCUGGAGGAGGCCAGGCCCUUGGUGGAAUUCUAUGAGGAGAUCAAGAAGUACGAGAAGCUGGAGACGGAGGAGGAGCGUGUGGCCCGCAGCCGGGAGAUCUUCGACUCAUACAUCAUGAAGGAGCUGCUGGCCUGCUCGCAUCCCUUCUCGAAGAGUGCCACUGAGCAUGUCCAAGGCCACCUGGGGAAGAAGCAGGUGCCUCCGGAUCUCUUCCAGCCAUACAUCGAAGAGAUUUGUCAAAACCUCCGAGGGGACGUGUUCCAGAAAUUCAUUGAGAGCGAUAAGUUCACACGGUUUUGCCAGUGGAAGAAUGUGGAGCUCAACAUCCACCUGACCAUGAAUGACUUCAGCGUGCAUCGCAUCAUUGGGCGCGGGGGCUUUGGCGAGGUCUAUGGGUGCCGGAAGGCUGACACAGGCAAGAUGUACGCCAUGAAGUGCCUGGACAAAAAGCGCAUCAAGAUGAAGCAGGGGGAGACCCUGGCCCUGAACGAGCGCAUCAUGCUCUCGCUCGUCAGCACUGGGGACUGCCCAUUCAUUGUCUGCAUGUCAUACGCGUUCCACACGCCAGACAAGCUCAGCUUCAUCCUGGACCUCAUGAACGGUGGGGACCUGCACUACCACCUCUCCCAGCACGGGGUCUUCUCAGAGGCUGACAUGCGCUUCUAUGCGGCCGAGAUCAUCCUGGGCCUGGAGCACAUGCACAACCGCUUCGUGGUCUACCGGGACCUGAAGCCAGCCAACAUCCUUCUGGACGAGCAUGGCCACGUGCGGAUCUCGGACCUGGGCCUGGCCUGUGACUUCUCCAAGAAGAAGCCCCAUGCCAGCGUGGGCACCCACGGGUACAUGGCUCCGGAGGUCCUGCAGAAGGGCGUGGCCUACGACAGCAGUGCCGACUGGUUCUCUCUGGGGUGCAUGCUCUUCAAGUUGCUGCGGGGGCACAGCCCCUUCCGGCAGCACAAGACCAAAGACAAGCAUGAGAUCGACCGCAUGACGCUGACGAUGGCCGUGGAGCUGCCCGACUCCUUCUCCCCUGAACUACGCUCCCUGCUGGAGGGGUUGCUGCAGAGGGAUGUCAACCGGAGAUUGGGCUGCCUGGGCCGAGGGGCUCAGGAGGUGAAAGAGAGCCCCUUUUUCCGCUCCCUGGACUGGCAGAUGGUCUUCUUGCAGAAGUACCCUCCCCCGCUGAUCCCCCCACGAGGGGAGGUGAACGCGGCCGACGCCUUCGACAUUGGCUCCUUCGAUGAGGAGGACACAAAAGGAAUCAAGUUACUGGACAGUGAUCAGGAGCUCUACCGCAACUUCCCCCUCACCAUCUCGGAGCGGUGGCAGCAGGAGGUGGCAGAGACUGUCUUCGACACCAUCAACGCUGAGACAGACCGGCUGGAGGCUCGCAAGAAAGCCAAGAACAAGCAGCUGGGCCAUGAGGAAGACUACGCCCUGGGCAAGGACUGCAUCAUGCAUGGCUACAUGUCCAAGAUGGGCAACCCCUUCCUGACCCAGUGGCAGCGGCGGUACUUCUACCUGUUCCCCAACCGCCUCGAGUGGCGGGGCGAGGGCGAGGCCCCGCAGAGCCUGCUGACCAUGGAGGAGAUCCAGUCGGUGGAGGAGACGCAGAUCAAGGAGCGCAAGUGCCUGCUCCUCAAGAUCCGCGGUGGGAAACAGUUCAUUUUGCAGUGCGAUAGCGACCCUGAGCUGGUGCAGUGGAAGAAGGAGCUGCGCGACGCCUACCGCGAGGCCCAGCAGCUGGUGCAGCGGGUGCCCAAGAUGAAGAACAAGCCGCGCUCGCCCGUGGUGGAGCUGAGCAAGGUGCCGCUGGUCCAGCGCGGCAGUGCCAACGGCCUCUGACCCGCCCACCCGCCUUUUAUAAACCUCUAAUUUAUUUUGUCGAAUUUUUAUUAUUUGUUUUCCCGCCAAGCGGAAAAGGUUUUAUUUUGUAAUUAUUGUGAUUUCCCGUGGCCCCAGCCUGGCCCAGCUCCCCCGGGAGGGGCCCGCUUGCCUCGGCUCCUGCUGCACCAACCCAGCCGCUGCCCGGCGCCCUCUGUCCUGACUUCAGGGGCUGCCCGCUCCCAGUGUCUUCCUGUGGGGGAAGAGCACAGCCCUCCCGCCCCUUCCCCGAGGGAUGAUGCCACACCAAGCUGUGCCACCCUGGGCUCUGUGGGCUGCACUCUGUGCCCAUGGGCACUGCUGGGUGGCCCAUCCCCCCUCACCAGGGGCAGGCACAGCACAGGGAUCCGACUUGAAUUUUCCCACUGCACCCCCUCCUGCUGCAGAGGGGCAGGCCCUGCACUGUCCUGCUCCACAGUGUUGGCGAGAGGAGGGGCCCGUUGUCUCCCUGGCCCUCAAGGCCUCCCACAGUGACUCGGGCUCCUGUGCCCUUAUUCAGGAAAAGCCUCUGUGUCACUGGCUGCCUCCACUCCCACUUCCCUGACACUGCGGGGCUUGGCUGAGAGAGUGGCAUUGGCAGCAGGUGCUGCUACCCUCCCUGCUGUCCCCUCUUGCCCCAACCCCCAGCACCCGGGCUCAGGGACCACAGCAAGGCACCUGCAGGUUGGGCCAUACUGGCCUCGCCUGGCCUGAGGUCUCGCUGAUGCUGGGCUGGGUGCGACCCCAUCUGCCCAGGACGGGGCCGGCCAGGUGGGCGGGCAGCACAGCAAGGAGGCUGGCUGGGGCCUAUCAGUGUGCCCCCCAUCCUGGCCCAUCAGUGUACCCCCGCCCAGGCUGGCCAGCCCCACAGCCCACGUCCUGUCAGUGCCGCCGCCUCGCCCACCGCAUGCCCCCUCGUGCCAGUCGCGCUGCCUGUGUGGUGUCGCGCCUUCUCCCCCCCGGGGCUGGGUUGGCGCACCCUCCCCUCCCGUCUACUCAUUCCCCGGGGCGUUUCUUUGCCGAUUUUUGAAUGUGAUUUUAAAGAGUGAAAAAUGAGACUAUGCGUUUUUAUAAAAAAUGGUGCCUGA